GCGUGCGUGAGCGUGCUCGUCUCCGCUGCCGCUGCCGCUGCCGCUGCCGGUGCCGCACCCGCGCCCUCUGCCGCCGCCGCCGCCGCCGCCCGGGGUCUCCAGGCUGAGGAGUGCGUCGGCCGCUGCCCAGCAGCGCCGCGAAUCGGGGAGCGGAGCCGCGGAGCCGGCGGGAGGGCGGGCGGGCGGGCGGACGGGCAGGUGAGCUCGCUGCGGGUCGGGCGGGCGGAUCGGCCCACGUCAGGCCCGGGCAGGCGGGCGGGCGGGCGCGGGUGGGGGGCGGGGGCGGCACUCCAGAGCCGGAAAUGGCGGCGACCCCCGGGCCGGGGCUGCGCGGGCGCUCGGGGCCGGAGCUGCUGCGACGCCGCGGCCUGGGCCGGGGCGGGGGCGCGGGAAGGUCGGCGCCGGGGCCUGCGGGAGCCGGGCCGGGCCGGGCCGGGGGUCUGAGCACCGUGGUGGGGGCUGGGGCGGCGCUCUCCGCGGGUCUCUUCGGGCCCGGACGCCCCCUCCGCUCCCCCAGGUCCCCGCGGCCGCCCCCAACCCCCCGGGGUCUCCUCUCCUGCGGGGGGACUGGAGAAGCUGGGCCAUCGCUGGUCUUAGGGAGGCAGAUAAUUUAGUCCCUGGGUCGUUGUGUUUAUAGCUCGGGGAAUUGAAAAUUGUUCUGUAACGCAUCGUAAAUUAAUCUUUCCGACGUUGUAAAUUCCAAAAAGCAUUUGGUUUGUUAGAAAAAACCUGUUUUCUCCGCUUUAUAAAAACAUUUGAAGCCAUGCUUUAUAUUGAACUCUUAAGGAGAGUAUUAGGAACUCGUCCGUUCAGGUUCUAACUUGUUGGUGUUAAGUGUCUGGAUUAAAGACUCUCUUUUUCGUGUGCCGAAGCCAUGAUUUCUCAAAUUCAUUCAGUUGUGUCAUACAGGAAAAGGAAGCAAAAAUUUCAGCUUUAUUUUUGUUUUCCGGCUUAGGCUUGGUUGGGAAGAUUUGAUGGUGGUUAGACACGUCUGCCCUUAUUUGCCUGUUUAGAAAAACCUAUUCUAAUGACAAAAACAGUUACAUUGCUCCCACUAUUGUCAUGGUUACCUGAAGGCAAAAGUUUACUCAAAGCUUCUGAGAUUUUAUGUUCGUUUAUUUGCUUCUCUUUUUAAAAAAAUGUCAGCUGAGUUUCAGGAAUGAGUAGUCUGUCAAACAAGAGAUGAAAUUAGAAGCCUGGAUCUAAGGGCUUUGGGGAAGUUUCGGUUGAGUUCCCCUUUCACUUGUGUCGGUGCUGUAGGACUCGGGGUGGCUCCAGCUGGCGUCUGGCCCAGCAGAGAGCUGUAGGGGCCCGCUCUGGUUGCUGGCUGUGUGGACUCUGAGGGACACCCCUGGCGAGGGUGUUAAUGAGCCUGCAGCGUCUGAGUCCACCCACCCUCAGACUGGCCCCUGACUCACUCUGCACCUGCCAUAUCAGCCUCCUUGCUAGUUCUGAACAGAGCCACAUGCUCUGUCCUUGGAUCUUCCUGGAAUGCCUGGUUCCUUAACCCCCUAGCCUGGCGACUGCCUGCCUGCCUUGCCACCCAGUUCCCUUCCUCGCUUAAUUUUCCCACAGCGCUGAAUCCUCCUAGUGUCCUGCUUAAUGCAUUUAUCAUACUUAAUAUUUUACUGUGAGUUAGUAAGGUCCGUGGAGAGAAUGUUUUGUGAAAAAAACAGUUGCUGGCACAUGAUCGGGGCCCAGUAAAUAUUUGUUCAGUGAAUGAACGUGAGGAGCUUAGCAGCAGCUGUGCGUGGUGCUGGCCUUGUCACCCGGAAGUCCUUGUCGGUGAGGACUGAGCAUGUAGAGGUAAGGGUUCCUGGAGUGUUGGCCCUCAGGACAGAGAGCCACCAUCUCUCACCUGCCCAAUGAGGAAAGACAGCCAGAAUAGCCUAACAUGGCAGACCAGAGACAGCGCUCACUGUCUACCUCUGGGGAGUCAUUGUACCACGUCCUUGGGUUGGACAAGAACGCAACCUCAGAUGACAUUAAAAAGUCCUAUCGGAAGCUUGCCUUGAAAUAUCACCCCGACAAGAACCCCGACAACCCGGAGGCCGCGGACAAGUUUAAGGAGAUCAACAACGCGCACGCCAUCCUCACGGACGCCACAAAAAGGAACAUCUACGACAAGUACGGCUCGCUGGGUCUCUACGUGGCCGAGCAGUUUGGGGAAGAGAACGUGAACACCUACUUCGUGCUGUCCAGCUGGUGGGCCAAGGCCCUGUUUGUCUUCUGCGGCCUCCUCACGUGCUGCUACUGCUGCUGCUGUCUGUGCUGCUGCUUCAACUGCUGCUGCGGGAAGUGUAAGCCCAAGGCGCCUGAAGGCGAGGAGACGGAGUUCUACGUGUCCCCCGAGGAUCUGGAGGCACAGCUGCAGUCUGACGAGAGGGAGGCCACAGACACGCCGAUCGUCAUACAGCCGGCAUCCGCCACCGAGACCACCCAGCUCACAGCCGACUCCCACCCCAGCUACCACACUGACGGGUUCAACUAAAUCCAGGAGGAGCUGUGGUCAGAGGAGGAGCCGGCGCCUGGCCACGCCAACCUUAGAAUCAUGAACUGUAGUCACAGAGAUGGGAAGGCAGCCUCCUGCCUGCCCUGGCCUUGCUGGGGCCCCUCCUGCCUCCACGCCCACCCAGCGUCGACCCUUGACCCACGAAGUGCGUAGCAUGCAGUAUUUAAAGCAGUGUAGCUACGGUCUUCUGUUUUUUUCCCUUUUUUAAUAGCAUGUAUGGGGUUCUGUUCCAUGUCUGUGUUGUGGACAUUCCGCGGCAUGACCGCGUGAACUGCACGGUGGAGCUGCCUCAGGGCUGUCGGUCAGGUUGGUCCAGUGAGGGGUGACUGCAGCCGGUCAGGUGGGCGAGGAGAAGGGGGGCUGCCCCUUUCCUACCUGUGCUUGAGGGGCCGGAGGCAGGUGCUGCCUGGCAGAGCUGUGUUACCGUCUUGGCCUCGGGGUCUGGUCCACACUCUGUGCUCCCAGCCUUGAGGCUGCAGUAGGACUCUGAUCUCACCUGCCAGAAGAGAGGCGGGGCCGCGUCCUCCUGGCGUCACCGGCGUCACUGUCAUUCCUUGGUGUCUGUGCUGGGCAUGGUUGGCUUGGGGGUCUGUGGUUUCCUGGGCCUUGUGGCAGGGUUUCUCCCGUGGGAGAAUUUGGUGUGGAAAGCAUAGGAGGCCCCUUCCGAGGUUGACACCGUGUCCUCCGCGGUGUUUCUCGCCUGGUCGUCUCGUCGUGUGGACGCUGCCGUUCUGGUUCUCGGAGGUGUGUCCUUCGCCGUGUUGGGGUUAUUUGUCUGUGUUCCUGCACUUUUCCCGGGCUCUGAGCUGGAUUGAUGGGGCCAGUCUCCCCCCUCCCAUCUUGAGGUCGUUCUCCACAUUCCUUCCAGCACACCUGUCCUUUCCAUAGCCCUUUUUGGACCUUUAGAACCACAGAUGAUAGGACCAGCCCAAUGAGCCACAGUCAGAGAGUAGAUUGUGCAUGUGUGAGCACCCAGCUACUGGGGACGGGGGCUCUCCCACGACCCCUCCUCCUGUGUUUGCCAGAGCUCCCAUCUGCCCCACUCGCCUUUGCCCCGUCAUCGAUGAUUCAGGCAGAGCCAGAUUCGUUAGGUCCCUGGAGGAAGGACUGACUGGACCAGAGGGACCCUCUGGCUCAGGAGGGUUGGGUCCCUGGGAGGCCGGCAGCCAGGCCACAGAAUCCACACGUGGACCAUUGUGGGUCCCUGGGAGGCCGGCAGCCAGGCCACGGAAUCCACACGUGGACCAUUGUGGGUCCCUUGGGAGGCCAGCAGCCAGACUACGGAAUCCACAUGUGGACCAUGGGAAGUCAGUCUCUUGCGUGUCCUAGACCUUGUGGGUGGCGCCCUGCAUAGGGGAGCAGGGGGAACGGGUCUGAUGUCCCUGUGCUGGCUGAGGGCUCAGAGCUGCCCGCACUCCGUAGCUCAUGGGAUGUGCUGGGCCUGCCUUUGGCGCCAUGCUGCAGACUCCAGUGGGCCUGGUUUCUGCAGAAUGUCCAUGGUGGCCGCUGCAGAGUUGCAGAGGUCCCUGUAGAGAUAAAGCUGAGGAGGAGGCUGUGUGUGAUGGCUCUGGCUCGGACCAACCAGAUGAGCCUCCUGAAGCCCCCUUCCCUGCCUGCCUGCUGACCCGUGGCCCCAGCUCACUCAUUGCCCUCAGCAGCCACCCGAGGCUGUGCAGAAGGGUAGGUUCAGGUUGACCAGGAAGCUGCCAAAAGGGACAUGGAUAUGAGGAUACAUCUGGACGUGCUUAGGAACAGGGUGCUGGUUGAGGGCCCCCAGCUGACCCCUACUGCAGAUCCGCAUGUGGACCAUGAGCCGGCUGCCAGCACUAGGUCCUGGGCAGCUUUGUUUGUCCCACUUUUCUUUGUUUCUUCUCACUAAAAUGAUCACGAAGACCUUUGACAAGAGGAGAGAUAUGCACUGUGAUAUUAAAUUAGAAAUAAUUUAUCAAAAUCAGACCUCUCCUAAAAGAAUAAGAAAUUCAUUGUUUGGCCCAUCCUGAAAGGUGAGGUGGCGAGACAGUGGGGUGCCUCCGUGCCGCUUCGUGCAGCAGCAAGUUCAGCCUGAGAUGCUGGCUGUACUCAGCCUUUGCAAUUUUUGUAGAUGUAGCUUAGGACGUGAGUUAUUUUUCCGCAGACUGGCCAAGAGCCAGGUUCUAAGCUUGGACCUAAGGUAGAAAGCUGCCCAUCGGGGGCCCUAGCUCAGCCCCACCAGGCCCUCUGUUGGGCCUGCACACAGCUCUGUGGCUAGAACACUCCAAGGCCCUUCGGUACCCAUCAGAGUGGGCCCCUUGCCAGGUGGCUUUUCAGUUACAGAGUCCAGUGGACCAUUUUGUAGAACCAUGCAGCUCCCUGCGGAAGGUGGGGUAGGGUGGGAAAGAGGAGCAGGUCUGGAGGUUUGUGGAACCCAGUCCCCUGCAGAAUCUGUAAAACCUAAUAAAUCAUGGUUGUGGCCAUUCUCACGGUGGUGAUUGUGAUUAGACGACCCCCGGGAAGCCCAGACACUCGGGGCCUGGAGUUCCUCCCCCUGCCUGACCUAGAAGCAGAACCGUUUUCAGCGCUCUGCCCUGUUGGCUUUAAGGCUUUGUCUUAAUUUAAGGAAAAAGAUCCUCCCGGGUUUUAUUUCUCUCUUUCUUGAGUGGACUGUUUCCCUAUAAUUAAAAGAGGUGGUGAGUCCUGGGGCAGCUUCCGCGCCUCCCUGUCCACGUGCUAACAGAUCAGGACGCCCCCAGCACCCCUGCCUGCUUUUGCUGGUGGCAGUGACGGGACCCCGACUCCUCACUCUCGGGCCGCAGACAAUGCUGUGAGCAAGUGUGGCCAUGGGCACAGAAUGUCCCUUUGGACGCCGCUGCUGGGGGCUGCCAGGGGCCCUCUGGGGUCGUGCUUUGAGGCCCGUCCGGUUCACGAGGGGGUCCGGGCAGCACUGACUGCUUCCGACCUGCAGGAGGCGUAGGAGCGGCCCUGCGGGCCCUUUCACGGCAGCUGCUGCUGUAUAGAUUUGUCUCCACUCAGUGACGUGGGAUUUUUUUGUCUUCCUUUUGGCUUUAUUUUUAAACUGCUUUAGAUAUUACUGCUCAGUGUUUGUGAACUUUCCUAGUUCUCUAUGUUGUUAGUGCAGCCAGCACCCAGUGGGGACCUACUAGAAAAAGGAACUGGCAUGCACACGUGCCCAGCAGGAAAAGCUUCGUCUUCACGUCGGCUGCUGCCAUCCAGAAGAGGCCCUGGAGCCUCACGCCGUCGAGGCUGCUCUCAGGCGUUCUGUUCCGGGCGAGGCUUGUGCUGCAAGGAAGGGCACCAGCAUGCAGGCUGCCACUGGAGGGUCCGGGUGCUGCGGGCAGAGUUCAGCGCUUGUCCACCCUCCCUUAGCUCUGACUCAGUGCAUCCUACUGUGGGGACAUCUCGUGAGGGGACACGAAAUGACUGAUCUCACCCUUUCCCAGUAUUCAGAGCUGUGAACCCCUGUGGCGCAGGACUGGCCUGUGUCUGUUAUUUUGGUUGUAAAUCAUUCUCCUGUGGAAUUGGCAAAAGCUACAUUUUUACUGUCCUUACCAGCAACAGUUUGCGUCGUCACAUGCUGUGAGUGUGGGCUGUGGUGUGUCCGUGUGUGUACAUAUGUGUAUAUGUAUAUAUCACGCAGCAGGAGUGUCAUUCAUGCUGCUGUCCCCUGGUGAAGUGACAAGUACAAUUAAAGGUGGCUCUGAAAUGGCCUCUGGUUUCUUGGGAGUCGGGCAGGGACCUGCAGGAGGCUUUCCCAGCAGGUGCACAGAAGGAAGCGCUGAGCCCACUGUGUGCAGAGGGUGUGUGCCCAGGGCACUGCCACGGCCCCCACCAGCAUUGGCCUCUGCUCUGCAGGGUGGGGUGCCCAUCCUGGGGGCUGUGUGUCAUGCUCACCUGACCCAGGUGUGUGUCCCGGUGUGAAAUCGAGGAGGGGACUGGAAGCCCUUCCCUGCCUUGAAACAUGAAAGCUGAUUUUCUGAGCAGCAGAUACGGUCAGUGGCAAAGCUGCAUCUGAAGGGCGGCCUGGGAAGGGGCCCUGUGCUGGCCCCGGGUCCGCCCCAGAGGAGUCCACACAGCACCACCUCCAGAAGGGGCUGGGCCCGGGGUCCUGCAGGCGGCACCUUUUGGUAGAGUUUGUUUCCCUGGAAAAUGGGGAAAAUGUUUCAAGCCAGGUGAGGGGGGAAGUUAACACUGAAAUAUGUAUUGUUUUUAAAAAUCAAAUGCACACGCAUGGAAGCUGCUUGUCCAUGCACUGGUUUUGUCACUGGCGUCCUGGAAUCCGACCGUGUUGGGGUGCAGGCGCUGUCAGACUCCGGCUGAUCCUGGCUCGAGCACACACAUCUAAGGGCCAGGCUGGUUCCGCAUGGUGAUCUCCGUCUUGUAUGUCUGAAUGUUGGCCUAAAAUAAAGAUUACUGUUGUAAAAUAAA